CUUUGUCUCCUUGCGGCCGGCGGGGUGCUGGGUUCCCGUCUGCUGCCUCUCGGAGAGUCCCGGGUGACUGCCGCAGGCUCCAUCGCCCUGUGGCCUGCAGGUAUUGCGAGAUUUAUAGGGAGGACGCUGGGACCCCCAAAAGCUGGGAAAUGGGACUAUUGGCAUUCAGGGAUGUGGCUCUAGAAUUCUCUCCAGAGGAGUGGGAAUGCCUGGACCCAGCUCAGCGGAGUUUGUAUAGGGAUGUGAUGUUAGAGAACUACAGAAACCUGAUCUCCCUUGGUGAGGAUAGCUUCAAUAUGCAAUUCCUAUUUCACAGUCUUGCUAUGUCUAAGCCAGAACUGAUCAUCUGUCUGGAGGCAAGGAAAGAGCCCUGGAACGUGAACACAGAGAAGACAGCCAGACACUCAGUUUUGUCUUCUUAUCUUACUGAAGACAUUUUGCCAGAGCAGGGCCUGCAAGUUUCAUUCCAAAAAGUGAUGCUGAGAAGAUAUGAAAGAUGUUGUCUUGAGAAAUUACGCUUAAGGAAUGACUGGGAAAUUGUGGGUGAGUGGAAAGGGCAGAAGGCAAGUUAUAAUGGACUUGACCUAUGCUCAGCAACUACUCAUAGCAAAAACUUUCAAUGCAAUAAAUGUGUGAAAGGUUUUAGUAAAUUUGCAAAUCUAAAUAAAUGUAAGAUAAGCCAUACUGGAGAAAAACCAUUCAAAUGCAAAGAAUGUGGCAAUGUCUCUUGCAUGUCUUUAAUAAUGACUCAACAGCAGAGAAUCCAUAUUGGAGAGAACCCGUACCAAUGUAAAAAAUGUGGCAAAGCCUUUAAUGAGUGCUCAUGCUUUACUGACUGUAAGAGAAUUCAUGUUGGAGAGAAACAUUGCAAAUGUGAAGAAUGUAAUAACAUUUUUAAGUCUUGCUCAAGUCUUGCUGUUGUUGAGAAAAAUCAUACUGAAAAGAAAACCUACAGAUGUGAAGAAUGUGGCAAAGCUUUUAACCUGUGCUCAGUUCUUACUAAACAUAAGAAAAUUCAUACUGGAGAGAAACCAUACAAAUGUGAAGAAUGUGGCAAAUCCUUUAAGUUGUUCCCAUACCUUACUCAACACAAGAGAAUUCAUAGUAGAGAGAAACCCUACAAGUGUGAAGAAUGUGGCAAAGUCUUUAAAUUGUUGUCAUACCUUACUCAACAUAGAAGAAUUCAUACUGGAGAGAAAACCUUCCGAUGUGAAGAAUGUGGAAAAGCCUUUAACCAGAGCUCACAUCUGACUGAACAUAGGAGAAUUCAUACUGGUGAGAAACCAUACAAAUGUGAGGAAUGUGGCAAAGCUUUUACCUGGUUCUCAUACCUUAUUCAGCAUAAGAGAAUUCAUACUGGGCAGAAACCCUACAAAUGUGAGGAAUGUGGCAAAGCUUUUACCUGGUUUUCAUACCUUACUCAACAUAAGAGAAUUCAUACUGGAGAGAAACCCUACAAAUGUGAUGAAUGUGGCAAAGCUUUUAACUGGUUUUCAUAUCUUACUAAUCAUAAGAGAAUUCAUACUGGAGAGAAACCCUACAAAUGUGAAGAAUGUGGCAAAGCCUUUGGCCAGAGCUCACACCUUUCUAAACAUAAGACAAUUCAUACCAGAGAGAAACCAUACAAGUGUGAGGAAUGUGGCAAAGCCUUUAACCACUCUGCACAACUUGCUGUACAUGAGAAAACUCAUACCUGAGAAAAACCCUACAAUUCUAAACAAUAUGGCAUAGUCUUUAAUACCUAUUCACAACUUCACAGCAGAAUAUUUUUACUGAAUAAGAGUGUUACAAAUGUAAUGACUGUCAAAAGGCCAUUUACAGUCUAUGAGCCUUUGAGUGCACUAAAAUGUUUAGGCUACGAACAAUACAAAUAGACCGGUUCAACACCUCCACUUAUAUCACAGCUCUUACUGUACACAGAAGAAUUUAUACUGGAGGGAAACCCUCCAGUUGCUCAAACUGUAUUCAAUUUCAAAGACUUUGUAUUGGAGAGAAACCCUACAAAUGUAAUAAAUGCAGAAACAACAUUUGUUCAAAAAAUAUACCUCAGAAAACACCAGAGUGUUCACACUAAAAACUGUUUUACAGAUGCAGUAAAUGUGAAAAAAUGUCUAAUCAAAAAUUACAUCAAAACACAUCCAAGAAUUCAUAGUAAAAAGCACUAAGUCACUGACACUUUCAGACAUUACUGUAAAUCUGAGUGUUGGUUAUAGAGAAUAAUUCAAAGUUAAGUUAAAGUAAGUAGGAGAUUCACCUUUUGGGGAAGUUAUAAUUACAUUUCAAGUAUACCUUUUGGUGCCAGGCACGGUGGCUCUUUCCUAUAGUUGCUGCACUUUUGGAUGCCGAGGUCGGGGGAUUGCUUGAGCCCAGGAGUUUGGGACCAGGCUGGGCAACAUGGCAAAACCUCAUCUCUACAAAAAGUAAAAUAAAAGCCAGGCUUGGUGGCACAUGCCUGUUGUCCCAGCUACUUGGAAGGCUCAGGUGGGAGGAUUGCUUGAGCCUGGAGGUUGAGGAUGCAGUGAGCUGCUAUCUGGCAACUUCACUCCUGCCUGGGCAACAGAGCAAGACCCUUUCUCAAUAAUAAUAAUAACAACAUAAUAAUAAAGUAUACUCGGUGCACUGAAAGAGUUUUAGCUUUUUUGAAAAUCACAUAUUUAUGUAAUUCAAGUCUUAAAUCACUUGAUACCAUGCCUUCAUUUCUAGUGUUUAUGUGAAGGCAUGAGGCCUACUGUUGCUACAUGAAAGCUGUGAGAGUUUCUUCUAUAUUCGGGUGGGUGUUGUUCAUAUCCUUUUCUUUGGAAGAUUAUGGACAUUGCAUUGUAAGCUUCCUGAAGAAAUUUAACUGGAGAGGCUCUUUGUACUUGUCUUAUAAUAGGGUUGUAAGUGAUUCAUGAGAUAGGUCUUCAGAGUACUAUUCUGCAUUAUAUUUAAGAAAGAAACAUUUGAGUUUUACAAGUCAGUUGUUUUUCCUAUUGCACAUUAAGGUAAUAAAAUUCAGUGGAUUUUGAAAUGCUCUUUUUAGACUGUUUGAACUUAAUUUGUUUUAAUAAGACAUUGUUUUAAUGUCUUUGGACCGUUGUACAUUAAGUGAUGCGUAUCCUACCACCAACGUUAACCUAUCUCACCUUAGUUACGGUUGUAGGUAACAAAUGGUAACAAUACAAUAGUGGGUAACAUGGUGGAAUAGUAUCUCUAAUGAUCCCUUCUCCCAGUGGCAUUAAACUUCAAAUAAUUUGAAAAAUAUUGUUCCCACACGUUACACCUUCAUUCUGUUUGCUCUUUUUGUAAUGACAGUGUCAUUAUUAAGGCUAUAAUAAAGCCUAUAUAGGAUUAUAAUCAAA